AUCUUCACCACUGCUCUCCCAGAGGUCCAGGUCCGGGAGAUGACAGUGGCUCCCAGAAAGCCCAGGAUUCAAUCGCUGAGAGAGUGCUUAGGCCCGAAUGCCGGCCCAAAUCGUUCUACUCACCGUGUCGGAGGCCGAGAGCGAUGAGAGUACAGGGAAGUGAGGAAGAGGGGGUGGCCGCCAGGCUCCUCCGCUUCCCUGGGUCCACCGCGGAUCCCUCCCGCUUGUCAGGAGGCGGCCAGCGGUCUCAGGACGGGCGCUUUGGAGCCGGCCCCAGGCAGCGUGUGUCGGUCGCCUAGUCUGGAGAACUAGUCCUCGACUCACGGUGAGGGAAUGGACCGACACGGGUAUUGUACCGCUGAGGGAAAGGAGCGGGACUCCGGACCUCCAGGAGUGCAAGGAUGAUGCUGAAAGGAAUAACAAGGCUUAUCUCUAGGAUCCAUAAGUUGGACCCUGGGCGUUUUUUACACAUGGGGACCCAGGCUCGCCAAAGCAUUGCUGCUCACCUAGAUAACCAGGUUCCAGUUGAGAGUCCGAGAGCUAUUUCCCGCACCAAUGAGAAUGACCCGGCCAAGCAUGGGGAUCAGCACGAGGGUCAGCACUACAACAUCUCCCCCCAGGAUUUGGAGACUGUAUUUCCCCAUGGCCUUCCUCCUCGCUUUGUGAUGCAGGUGAAGACAUUCAGUGAAGCUUGCCUGAUGGUAAGGAAACCAGCCCUAGAACUUCUGCAUUACCUGAAAAACACCAGUUUUGCUUAUCCAGCUAUACGAUAUCUUCUGUAUGGAGAGAAGGGAACAGGAAAAACCCUAAGUCUUUGCCAUGUUAUUCAUUUCUGUGCAAAACAGGACUGGCUGAUACUACAUAUUCCAGAUGCUCAUCUUUGGGUGAAAAAUUGUCGGGAUCUUCUGCAGUCCAGCUACAACAAACAGCGCUUUGAUCAACCUUUAGAGGCUUCAACCUGGCUGAAGAAUUUCAAAACUACAAAUGAGCGCUUCCUGAACCAGAUAAAAGUUCAAGAGAAGUAUGUCUGGAAUAAGAGAGAAAGCACUGAGAAAGGGAGUCCUCUGGGAGAAGUGGUUGAACAGGGCAUAACACGGGUGAGGAACGCCACAGAUGCAGUUGGAAUUGUGCUGAAAGAGCUAAAGAGGCAAAGUUCUUUGGGUAUGUUUCACCUCCUAGUGGCCGUGGAUGGAAUCAAUGCUCUUUGGGGAAGAACCACUCUGAAAAGAGAAGAUAAAAGCCCGAUUGCCCCCGAGGAAUUAGCACUUGUUCACAACUUGAGGAAAAUGAUGAAAAAUGAUUGGCAUGGAGGCGCCAUUGUGUCGGCUUUGAGCCAGACUGGGUCUCUCUUUAAGCCCCGGAAAGCCUAUCUGCCCCAGGAGUUGCUGGGAAAGGAAGGAUUUGAUGCCCUGGAUCCCUUUAUUCCCAUCCUGGUUUCCAACUAUAACCCAAAGGAAUUUGAAAGUUGUAUUCAGUAUUAUUUGGAAAACAAUUGGCUUCAACAUGAGAAAGCUCCUACAGAAGAAGGGAAAAAAGAGCUGCUGUUCCUAAGUAACGCGAACCCCUCGCUGCUGGAGCGGCACUGUGCCUACCUCUAAGCCAAGAUCACAGCAUGUGAGGAAGACAGUGGACAUCUGCUUUAUGCUGGACCCAGUAAGAUGAGGAAGUCGGGCAGUACACAGGAAGAGGAGCCAGGCCCUUGUACCUAUGGGAUUGGACAGGACUGCAGUUGGCUCUGGACCUGCAUUAAAAUGGGUUUCACUGUGAAUGCGUGACAAUAAGAUAUUCCCUUGUUCCUAAAACUUUAUAUCAGUUUAUUGGAUGUGGUUUUUCACAUUUAAGAUAAUUAUGGCUCUUUUCCUAAAAAAUAAAAUAUCUUUCUAAAGUGUUGUGUUAGAUUAAUAAUAUGGAAGGAGUCUUUAGAUUGGCCAAAUUGCAUUUCUCUGAUAUUCCUCUUGUUGCAGGUCAGAAGAGAUCAAUUCUACAGAAAUUUCCAGUGGUUCUGUUGAGGCUUUAUGGAAUUCAGCAUGUCAAAAUUCACAGCUGGCUGGGCACAGUGGCUCAUGCCUGUAAUCCCAGCACUUUGGAAGCCCAAGGCGGGCAGACUGCUUGAGUUCAGGAGUUUGCAACCAGCCUGGGCAACAUGGUGAAAACCUGUCUCUACUAAAAAUACAAAAAUUAGCCGGGCACGGUGGCAUGCGCCUGUAAUCCAAGCUACUUGGGAGGCUGAGGCAGGAGAAUUGCUUCAACUUGGGAGGCGGAUGUUGCAGUGAGCCAAAAUUGCACCACUGCACUCCAGCCUGGGCAGCAGAGCAAGACUCCGUCUCAAAAUAAAUAAAUAAAUAAAUAAAUAAAUAAAUAAUAAA